CGUCCGGCGGCGGCGGCAGCGGCAGCGGCAGCGGCGCUGAGUUUUGUCUCCCGGGCCGUCUGGGCGCGCGCGGGUGUCCCAGAAUGAAAUAUGACUGAGGACUCUCAGAGAAACUUUCGUUCAGUAUAUUAUGAGAAAGUGGGGUUUCGUGGAGUUGAAGAAAAGAAAUCAUUAGAAAUUCUCCUAAAAGAUGACCGUCUGGAUACUGAGAAACUUUGUACUUUUAGUCAGAGGUUCCCUCUCCCGUCCAUGUACCGUGCAUUGGUAUGGAAGGUGCUUCUAGGAAUCUUGCCUCCACACCACGAGUCCCAUGCCAAGGUGAUGAUGUAUCGUAAGGAGCAGUACUUGGAUGUCCUUCAUGCCCUGAAAGUCGUUCGCUUUGUUAGUGAUGCCACACCUCAGGCUGAAGUCUAUCUCCGCAUGUAUCAGCUGGAGUCUGGGAAGUUACCUCGAAGUCCCUCUUUUCCACUGGAGCCAGAUGAUGAAGUGUUUCUUGCCAUAGCUAAAGCCAUGGAGGAAAUGGUGGAAGAUAGUGUCGACUGUUACUGGAUCACCCGACGCUUUGUGAACCAAUUAAAUACCAAGUACCGGGAUUCCUUGCCCCAGUUGCCAAAAGCGUUUGAACAAUACUUGAAUCUGGAAGAUGGCAGACUGCUGACUCAUCUGAGGAUGUGUUCCGCGGCGCCCAAACUUCCUUAUGAUCUCUGGUUCAAGAGGUGCUUUGCGGGAUGUUUGCCUGAAUCCAGUUUACAGAGGGUUUGGGAUAAAGUUGUGAGUGGAUCCUGUAAGAUCCUAGUUUUUGUAGCUGUCGAAAUUUUAUUAACCUUUAAAAUAAAAGUUAUGGCACUGAACAGUGCAGAGAAGAUAACAAAGUUUCUGGAAAAUAUUCCCCAGGACAGCUCAGACGCGAUCGUGAGCAAGGCCAUUGACUUGUGGCACAAACACUGUGGGACCCCGGUCCAUUCAAGCUGAACGCACCCGCUGGUUGUGGACCGUCUGCCAGGCACCACAAUCAUUCCUGGACCCCCGAGGGCCUCUGAGUUUGAGACGCUGGCUGAGAUCAAAUGAUAAGAAUUCCAAUUUUUGUUUUCCUAAGUCUUUCAUCUGCUAAUCUACCCAACAUGAACCACGGGCCACAUGAAGGGCCAGACACAUUCUUAAGCGGCUCACAGCCUAGAGGUGCACAUCUGUGAUUACAAUGUGCAAGGUAAAACUGGAUCAACAGUUUCCAAGGACUGGCAUGUAAUAAAAUAUCCUCAAAACAACAAGCAAGUUGGGCGUGACUUAGACUUUCACUGCCCAUGUAGAAGGCACUGUACAUUCUUGCAGCAUCUCAGUUGGCCAGCAAGAGGUGAGUCAGAAAAAAACCAUUCAGCAGCCACAUGGAAGUGGGGCUCACUGGGCACAAGGCAAAACUGUGAAGAAGAUAAAGUGUCUGUGGUUCUGCAUUGACUCUAUUCCCUGGAGUCCUCCCCUCUCGAGUUCCUAGAAUUAUGUUAUCACUCUUGCUCUAUCUCAUUCCUAUCAAGACCUGUUUUAGAAAUGGGUGCCACAGACUCAGUUACAUUCAAAUGUAAACCCAUUCAUUCAUUUAGCAAGUUACUUAUUAGUGCCAGUGCUGUGUCAGGUUCUACAUUAGGUACCAGAGUACAGUGAUGAGCAAAACCAGUCCCUGCCCUUCUGGAACAGAGAAGACUGGAAGAGGAUGGGGGUAGCCAUUAAUCAAACAGUCACAGAAAUGAGUGCAAAAUGUAGCUGGAGUAAGGGCUUCCAUGGUGAGGCACUUGGUGCAGGGAUCUCUGGAUCUGACCAAAUCAGGAGGUCAGGAAAGGCUUCCAGGAGGAAGUGACACUGUGCCCAGAGCUCAGGGAUGGAAGAAGGAUGCUCCUUCUGGGCAGAGAGUAAGGAGAGAAGAUUGGUGGGAAGGAGGGCAGGGGCCAGAUGCCGUGGGUGUGAUUUGGAUCUGUGUCCCUGCCAAUCACAUGUUGAAUUGUAGUCCCCAGUGUUGGAGGUGGAGCCUGGUGGGACAUGAUUGGAUCAUGGGGGUAGUUUUUCAUGAACGGUUUAGUACCAACCACUUGGUGCUGUUCUAGUGAGUUGAGUGCAUUCUCGCGAGAUCUGGUUGUUUAAAAGUGUGUAGCACCCUUCCCUCUUGCUCCUGCUCCUCCAAUGUGAGACUCCUUGCUUUCCCUCUGUUUUCCACCAUGAUUGGAAGCUUCCUGAGGCCUCACCAGAGGCAGAUGCCAGCAUCAUGCUUCCUGUGCAGCCUGCAGAACUGUGAGCCAAUUAAACCUCUUUUCGUUAUAAACUA